CCCCCCAGAGUGCUGGGAUUACAAGAUUGAGCCACUGCGCUCAGUAUGUAUCUGGCCUAGCUUCCACCCUUACUACUCUUUCCCCAUGCCUGCUACACCAGAGCCGCCCAGGCCUUGGUUAUUUUUUUUUCUAAUGUGCCAAGCUCAUUCCCACUUUAGGGCCUUUGCAUCCACUGUUCCCUCUUUCCAGAACAUUCCACACACAUACUCUUUGCUCUACAUUAUAGCUGGCUCCUUCUCAUCCCUUAGUUUUCAGCUUAAAAGUCACUUCCUGAGAGGCCUUCCCUGAUUUCUGCAGCUAAGGAAUCCUCCCUCCCCUACCACCAUUAUUCUGUCAUUUCCUCCUUUUUCUUCAUAGCACCUGCCACAACUUGUAAUUAUAGACUCCUUUGCUUAUUGGCUUUUUCUUCCAGGGCUCUAUGAACCACAUGAGGGCAGGAACUAUCUGUUCCCGUCCCCUGGCACCUAGCAUAGGGCUCUCCAUAUUUAAGGAAUGAGUGAGCUGAUAACUGAAGUGAGGUUGGAAGGCAGGGUCCCUCCACUCUGUUUAUGUAGCUGCCUCCUUGCAUGGAAGGCUGGGCCCCAACUGGGGCAGGAUCCGAUUUCCACUGAGGGCUGGAACCCCCACCCCACCCCCCAGGAAGUGUUCUCAGCCCUGGGCCCUGGGUGCCAGGAAAUUUGGCCUAGGUAUCAGGGAGGGGCGGGAAUCCAGCCUCCCUGCUGCCCAGCUGGGGAGGUCCCUGUCUCUUCCUAGCCGGGCACCGUUGCCCCGCCUGUCCUGGGGUGCACGCGAAAAUGAGGAAAGACCCGGACUCCUUCCUGAAGUCUGCACGGCUGCAGCGGCUGCCAUCGUCGUCGUCGGAGAUGGGCAGCCAAGACGGGUCGCCGCUACGCGAGACGCGCAAAGACCCGUUCUCCGCCGCAGCGGCCGAGUGCUCCUGCCGCCAGGAUGGGCUCACGGUCAUCGUCACGGCCUGUCUCACCUUCGCUACCGGUGUCACCGUGGCGCUGGUCAUGCAGAUCUACUUCGGGGACCCCCAGAUCUUCCAGCAGGGUGCCGUGGUGACCGAUGCUGCCCGCUGCACUUCACUGGGCAUCGAGGUGCUCAGUAAACAGGGAUCUUCUGUGGACGCAGCGGUGGCAGCAGCCUUGUGUUUGGGUAUCGUGGCUCCACACAGUUCUGGCCUGGGCGGUGGGGGCGUGAUGCUGGUACAUGACAUCCGACGAAAUGAGAGCCACCUAAUUGAUUUCCGGGAGUCCGCACCAGGGGCCCUCAGGGAAGAGACCCUGCAAAGAUCCUGGGAGACCAAGCCUGGGCUCUUGGUGGGGGUUCCCGGAAUGGUGAAGGGGCUACAUGAAGCUCACCAGCUCUAUGGCAGGCUGCCAUGGUCCCAAGUCCUGGCCUUUGCAGCAGCUGUGGCCCAAGAUGGCUUCAACGUGACUCAUGAUCUAGCCCGUGCCCUGGCUGAACAGCUGCCACCCAACAUGUCCGAGCGCUUCCGGGAGACGUUCCUGCCAUCGGGCCGCCCGCCACUACCUGGCUCGUUGCUGCAUCGGCCCGACCUGGCUGAGGUGCUGGAUGUACUUGGCACCUCCGGCCCGGCUGCCUUCUACGCAGGUGGCAACCUCACACUGGAGAUGGUGGCCGAGGCUCAGCACGCAGGGGGUGUCAUAACCGAAGAGGACUUCAGCAAUUACAGCGCCCUUGUGGAGAAGCCUGUGUGUGGCGUGUACAGAGGCCACCUGGUUCUUAGUCCCCCACCUCCGCACACGGGCCCUGCCCUCAUCAGUGCUCUCAACAUCCUGGAGGGCUUCAAUCUCACCAGCCUGGUAUCCCGAGAACAGGCUCUUCACUGGGUGGCAGAGACCCUGAAGAUUGCAUUAGCCCUGGCCAGCAGACUGGGAGAUCCCGUCUAUGAUUCUACCAUCACUGAGAGCAUGGAUGACAUGCUCAGCAAGGUGGAGGCCGCCUACCUCCGGGGCCAUAUCAAUGACUCCCAGGCAGCCCCUGCCCCACUCCUGCCUGUCUAUGAACUAGACGGAGCUCCCACGGCUGCCCAGGUGCUGAUCAUGGGACCUGAUGACUUCAUUGUGGCCAUGGUUAGCUCCCUGAACCAGCCCUUUGGCAGCGGCCUUAUCACCCCCUCGGGGAUCCUGCUCAACAGCCAGAUGCUGGACUUCUCCUGGCCCAACCGGACAGCUAACCACUCUGCACCCAGCCUGGAGAAUUCAGUGCAGCCAGGGAAGCGGCCACUCUCUUUCCUGCUGCCCACAGUGGUCCGACCCGCGGAGGGGCUCUGUGGAACCUACCUCGCUCUGGGGGCCAAUGGAGCUGCGCGGGGCCUCAGCGGCCUGACACAGGUUCUGCUGAAUGUCCUGACCUUGAACCGGAACCUGAGUGACAGCCUGGCCCGCGGCCGCCUACACCCGGACCUGCAGUCCAACCUCCUGCAGGUGGACAGUGAGUUCACAGAGGAAGAGAUUGAGUUCCUGGAAGCCAGGGGUCACCACGUGGAGAAAGUAGAUGUCUUAUCCUGGGUCCAUGGCAGCCGAAGGACCAACAACUUCAUCAUCGCUGUUAAGGACCCUCGGAGCCCAGAUGCAGCUGGAGCCACCAUCCUGUAGAGCAGCGGGGUGGGGCGGGGUCUCUGCUCCCCCACUUUGCAUGUUCCCAGAGUCCCUCCUUCUCCCAGGUUUGGUCUCAGGGGGACCCCAGGGAUGCCCCAGAUCAGGGGCCAGAGGGGAUGCUUAGCAAACCCAAUCCCAGAGUAACUGGAAAAUUCUCCAUCAGGAGGCCUGUGGUGGUGGUGGUGGUGGUGGUGGUGGUGGUGGUGGUGGUGAGUGUCAGCAUCUACAGUACAGCCAGGCAGGCAGGACCUUGAGGAAUCAGACUAUCUGUCUGUGUGUCACCUCUCCUCCUUCAGCCAUGCUGGCCCCGAGCUUAGGGAUGUGCUUGCAAACCCUUCUCAAGGGUCUCACAACCCCAACAUCUUCAGACUGGCCUGACCUGGGCCUUGUCUUCCAGUUCCUUUCUCCCAUUCCCAGCCUCAUUUCUUAAAUGACUAGGAAUUUUUUAAUGGACCAUCAUAGGGAGGGGGUGCUCCUCUUUUCCCACCAGGUUGAGGUGGGGGCCUUGCAUCGGGGGUCCCCAGGGUAUGGGGUAGGGGUGGGGGUGGGCACCAGCUCAGGGGCUUCCAUUUGCAAAGGGAAAUUAAAGAAAGAAUGUUGCUUAA